CAUGUCGCUCAUGGUCAUCAGCAUGGCGUGUGUUGGGUUCUUCUUGCUGCAGGGGGCCUGGACACAUGAGGGUGGACAGGACAAGCCCUUGCUGUCUGCCUGGCCCAGCGCUGUGGUGCCUCGAGGAGGACAUGUGACUCUUCUGUGUCGCUCUCGUCUUGGGUUUACCAUCUUCAGUCUGUACAAAGAAGAUGGGGUGCCUGUCCCUGAGCUCUACAACAAAAUAUUCUGGAAGAGCAUCCUCAUGGGCCCUGUGACCCCUGCACACGCAGGGACCUACAGAUGUCGGGGUUCACACCCGCGCUCCCCCAUUGAGUGGUCGGCACCCAGCAACCCCCUGGUGAUCGUGGUCACAGGUCUAUUUGGGAAACCUUCACUCUCAGCCCAGCCGGGCCCCACGGUUCGCACAGGAGAGAACGUGACCUUGUCCUGCAGCUCCAGGAGCUCAUUUGACAUGUACCAUCUAUCCAGGGAGGGGAGGGCCCAUGAACCUAGGCUCCCUGCAGUGCCCAGCGUCGAUGGAACAUUCCAGGCUGACUUUCCUCUGGGCCCUGCCACCCACGGAGGGACCUACACAUGCUUCAGCUCUCUCCAUGACUCACCCUAUGAGUGGUCAGACCCGAGUGACCCACUGCUUGUUUCUGUCACAGGAAACUCUUCAAGUAGUUCAUCUUCACCCACUGAACCAAGCUCCAAAACUGGUAUCCGCAGACACCUGCACAUUCUGAUUGGGACCUCAGUGGCUAUCAUCCUCUUCAUCAUCCUCUUCUUCUUUCUCCUUCAUUGCUGCUGCUCCAACAAAAAGAAUGCUGCUGUAAUGGACCAAGAGCCUGCCGGGGACAGAACAGUGAACAGGGAGGACUCUGAUGAUCAAGACCCUCAGGAGGUGACAUAUGCACAGUUGGAUCACUGCGUUUUCACACAGACAAAAAUCACUUCCCCUUCUCAGAGGCCCAAGACACCUCCAACAGAUACCACCAUGUACAUGGAACUUCCAAAUGCUAAGCCAAGAUCAUUGUCUCCUGCCCAUAAGCACCACAGUCAGGCCUUGAGGGGAUCUUCUAGGGAGACAACAGCCCUGUCUCAAAACCGGGUUGCUAGCUCCCAUGUACCAGCAGCUGGAAUCUGAAGGCAUCAGUCUUCAUCUUAGGGGAUCGCUCUUCCUCACACCACAAAUCUGAACAUGCCUCUCUCUUGCUUACAAAUGUCUAAGGUCCCCACUGCCUGCUGGAGAGAAGACACACACCUUUGCUUAGCCCACAAUUCUCUAUUUCACUUGACCCCUGCCCACCUCUCCAACUGAACUGGCUUACUUCCUAGUCUACUUGAGGCUGCAAUCACACUGAGGAACUCACAAUUCCAGACAUACAAGAGGCUCCCUCUUAACAUGGCACUGAGACACGUGCUGUUCCACCUUCCCUCAUGCUGUUUCACCUUUCCUCAGACUAUUUUCCAGCCUUCUGUCAGUCAGCAGUGAAACUUAUAAAAUUUUUUGUGAUUUCAAUGUAGCUGUCUCCUUUUCAAAUAAACAUGUCUGCCCUCAUUGCUUUAGGUAAUGUGACACUAUUCGCUGAAAGAAACCGCUGUUAUCAUUACCAUGUCCACAUAACCCCAUCUGUUAUCCACUGGGUUC